GCGCCGAGUCCUUUUGUCCAAGAUGGCGGCGCCGGGGGCGCUGCCUCCUCGGCCGCCGCCUCCGCCGCCGCCGCUGUGAGAAACCUACGGGCCGCCCGCCCGCCGCGCCAGCGCCAUGAAGCGGCAGAGCGAGCGAGACUCUAGCCCGAGCGGGCGCGGCUCGUCAUCGUCCGCCAAGCGUCCGCGGGAGCGCGAACGGGAGGCGGAGGCGGGCGGGCGGCGGGCGGCGCACAAGGCCUCUGGCGGCGCCAAGCACCCGGUUCCAGCGCGGGCCCGCGACAAACCCCGCGGCAGCGGAAGCGGCGGGGGCGGGCAUCGCGACGGCCGCGGCACCGGGGACGCGAAUCACCGCGCGAGUAGCGGGCGCUCCUCGGGCUCCGGCGCUGGCGGCGGGGGACGCGGCGGCAAGGCCUCGGGGGACCCGGGCGCCUCCGGCAUGUCGCCCCGCGCGUCUCCUCUGCCGCCGCCUCCGCCACCGCCUGGGGCCGAGCCCGCGUGUCCCGGCUCAUCCGCGGCCGCGCCUGAGUACAAGACGUUGCUCAUCAGCAGCUUGAGCCCCGCGCUGCCCGCCGAGCACCUCGAGGACCGGCUCUUCCACCAGUUCAAGCGCUUCGGCGAGAUCAGCCUCCGCCUGUCGCACACGCCUGAGCUGGGCCGUGUGGCCUACGUGAAUUUCCGGCACCCACAGGACGCACGCGAGGCCCGCCAGCACGCCCUGGCCCGGCAGCUGCUGCUCUACGACCGCCCGCUCAAGGUAGAGCCCGUGUACCUGCGUGGCGGCGGCGGGAGCAGUCGGCGAAGUAGCAGCAGCAGCGCCGCCGCUUCCACGCCUCCCCCAGGGCCGCCCGCGCCCGCCGACCCGCUCGGCUACCUCCCGCUACACGGAGGCUACCAGUACAAGCAGCGCUCGCUGUCCCCCGUCGCUGCCCCGCCCCUGCGGGAGCCCCGUGCCCGUCACGCCGCCGCAGCCUUCGCCCUGGAUGCCGCUGCUGCCGCCGCCGUGGGACUGUCCCGGGAGCGGGCCCUGGACUACUACGGGCUGUACGACGACCGUGGGCGCCCCUAUGGCUACCCAGCUGUGUGUGAGGAGGACCUGAUGCCCGAGGAUGACCAGCGGGCCACGCGCAACCUCUUCAUUGGUAACCUGGACCACAGCGUAUCUGAGGUGGAGCUGCGAAGGGCCUUCGAGAAAUAUGGCAUCAUCGAGGAGGUGGUCAUCAAGAGGCCUGCCCGUGGCCAGGGCGGUGCCUAUGCCUUCCUCAAGUUCCAGAACCUGGACAUGGCCCAUAGGGCUAAGGUGGCCAUGUCGGGCCGAGUGAUUGGUCGCAACCCCAUUAAGAUAGGCUAUGGCAAGGCCAACCCCACCACUCGUCUCUGGGUGGGUGGCCUGGGACCUAACACGUCACUGGCGGCUCUGGCCCGAGAGUUUGACCGCUUUGGGAGCAUUCGGACCAUUGAUCACGUCAAAGGAGAUAGCUUUGCCUAUAUUCAGUACGAGAGCUUGGACGCAGCCCAGGCCGCCUGUGCUAAAAUGAGGGGUUUUCCCUUGGGUGGACCAGACCGCAGGCUCCGCGUGGAUUUUGCCAAAGCAGAGGAGACUCGGUACCCCCAGCAGUACCAGCCCUCGCCACUCCCUGUGCAUUAUGAGCUGCUCACAGAUGGAUACACCCGGCACCGCAACCUGGACGCCGACCUGGUGCGGGACAGGACGCCCCCACACCUUCUGUACUCAGACCGAGACCGGACUUUUUUGGAAGGGGACUGGACCAGCCCCAGUAAAAGCUCUGACCGCCGAAACAGCCUUGAGGGCUACAGUCGCUCAGUGCGCAGCCGGAGUGGUGAGCGUUGGGGGGCAGAUGGAGACCGUGGUUUGCCCAAGCCCUGGGAAGAGAGGCGGAAACGGAGAAGCCUUUCCAGUGACCGUGGGAGGACAACCCAUUCACCAUAUGAGGAACGGAGUAGGACCAAGGGCAGUGGGCAGCAGUCAGAGCGGGGCUCCGACCGCACCCCUGAGCGCAGCCGCAAGGAGAACCACUCCAGUGAAGGGACCAAGGAGUCCAGCAGCAACUCCCUCAGCAACAGCAGACAUGGGGCUGAGGAACGGGGCCACCACCACCACCACCACGAGGCUGCAGACUCUUCCCACGGGAAGAAGGCAAGAGACAGCGAGCGCAAUCACCGGACCACAGAGGCCGAGCCCAAGCCUCUGGAAGAGCCAAAACACGAGACCAAAAAGCUGAAGAAUCUUUCAGAGUACGCUCAGACACUACAGCUGGGUUGGAAUGGGCUUCUGGUGUUGAAAAACAGCUGCUUCCCCACGUCUAUGCAUAUCCUAGAGGGGGACCAGGGGGUGAUCAGCAGUCUCCUCAAAGACCACACUUCUGGGAGCAAGCUGACCCAGCUGAAGAUCGCCCAGCGCCUUCGACUGGACCAGCCCAAGCUUGACGAGGUCACACGACGCAUCAAGCAGGGGAGCCCCAACGGCUAUGCGGUCCUCUUAGCCACCCAGGCAACCCCCAGUGGGCUUGGCACUGAGGGGAUGCCCACAGUAGAGCCCGGUCUGCAGAGGCGGCUUCUCAGGAACCUGGUCUCCUACUUGAAACAGAAGCAGGCCGCAGGGGUGAUCAGCUUGCCAGUGGGGGGGUCCAAGGGCAGAGACGGCACAGGCAUGCUCUACGCCUUCCCACCCUGCGACUUUUCCCAGCAGUACCUCCAGUCAGCACUAAGGACAUUGGGCAAGCUAGAAGAAGAACACAUGGUGAUAGUCAUCGUCAGAGACACUGCCUAGCCCAAGCCUGUCUUUCCCAGCGUCAUGUUUGUGUCACAAAAGCAGUUAUUUUAAAAUCUGAUCCCCUCUCUACCCUACCACUUUGGUUUGAAUUAUCUCCUGGGUUAUUUUGGUUCAUUUGGGUGGGGAUCAAAGUCCUGUCCACCACCAAAACUAAGUUCUUAGAUUUUGGGGGAUUUUUUUUUUUAAACGAUGAGAAGGGAAUCCGGUUAUGUUGAUUUCUAGUGUACAAGAUACUGUCUGCUGUGGUUCUGUAUUUUUUUAUUUUUUGACCAACUGUAUGGAAAGUUGUCAGUAAAACCUUUGACAGAGGAUGGAUUUUUAAACCUGUUCAGAGUCCUGGUUUAAUCAAUCAAGCUAAAAGAAUCGAAGACAUCCCUAGUGCAUGUACACGAAUGCCCUACGUCAUCCUUCCAGCACCACUGCUGCAUGGGUCACUCUCGGCCUCUCAAUUCUUCAGGCUCAGUCUGGACUCUACUUACACUCAUUUUUAUCUUGGCUGACAGCAGGCAAGCUUCAGUUUGGGCUGUGGACGCUGCCACACAAGCCUGAGUAGAGCCCAUGCAAAGGAAGGGAUGGGGUGAGCGCAAGGCCUGUGGUCAGCAGCUACUGAUGGUUUUUUCUGCCUUAAACCGUGUGUGUGUCCAUCAUCAUCAGUUUGAGCUGUGGCUGUUUGUUUGGGACAGAGUGCCCACUCAGCAUGUUUGGCAGCAGGUAGCCUUCAGCAGCUGUGUAGUCUUGUACAAGGAGAAGCUGUGCACUGUUGAUGCCAGGGGGUCUCGGGGCCCCUGAUCUGUCCAGGCUCCUGGUUCGGCCUACUUUCUAGCCUCACUCAGCCCAGGGAUAGCCAGUGUUGGGAGACAGAGUUGCCUCAGGUUCCCAGGGGCCCGGGAGUCCAAAUACUGGAAUGGAGGGUUGGAGGCAGCCUUCCUUGGAUUUACUCAUGAACUUUGCCUAGUUGUUUGUGAUUUUUGGCUUUCUCUGGUCGUUCAGGGGUGAUGGGUAAUAGAGCAGGCCCGUGUCCAGUCAUACCUAGAGAUUUGUGGGGGGAUACUGAACCUCUAGACUGAAGUACUUACCGGGGAGCACAGUGGACUAGGGGAUGCCCUUGAUAAUGACGGUUUCCUAGGUGCAAGAUCAGAGCAUGUGCCUACACCUUGUGCCCUGAUGCCGAGGUGGAGACCAUUGGGAAAUAAUUAAUAGAUAUUUUUCUGGGGGGAAAUCACAAGUCACUGAGGUGUUUGUUUGUUUGUUAGGCAGUGCUAGAGCUUGAAGCCACUCAAGCCAGUUGGGGAGGAAAGGGAUGCGGAGGUACCCUCUAGCUGGGAAGAAGGGUGAGAUUCCGUCUUCUUCCCUGUCUCAAGUAAGUAAGGAAGGUACUGCGGACAGUGUGGGCCAGGGAGGAAAACCAGAGCACACAGUUUUGUCACCAUGGAACACCCCAAAUGCCAUUCUUCAGCGUGUCUGGUACCUUGGAUGUUCAAACAGGGAACACUGUCAGGGCUGAGGAGAACAGAAGCUCUGGUAAGCGAAUGAGCCCCUAGAUGAUAACCAGGAACUCCAGGUUCUGCUGGCCGUGGCAUCCUCUCUCCAGGUCUGCUCCCUUACCGGAGCUAGGAUAAGGUAGCAUGAGUGACACCUGAGAUUAGAGGCUGGGGCUCACUGCAGGCUGUGGAGAGGUCAUGCUGGUCCACAGGAACACUUGGCAGUGCUCUCGUAGACCCCUCGGUGAUGUGGAAUGGACAGGUGCCUCGCAAGAGAGCAAGCACGUUCAUAACAAAACAGCAACACAAAGACAUGUUAAGCAUGUUUAUUUAUUUGCCUGUUUUUGUUUUUUUACUUGAGCUGUGGUCACAGCUGCCAGGUACCUAAGCAAGUCAGUUGGGUACAGCAGGACACGCCACCAUUCCAGGGUAGCUGGUACCGCCAGAAACAGGAGUGGGUCUUGUCCUGUUGCAGGCACACUGCAGUGGUUUUCCUGCAGCUCUCCAACAAACGCCUGAGUCACAGGCCAGAGCUGCCUUGGUAUGUUGUUAAGUCCAAAACUUCUUCUCUGGGCUACCUAUCUUCCUUCAUGAAGCAGGUGCUCAGGACCCGGAAGAAUCAUCUACCUCCCAGCUUUGUGAGACAGAACCAAGUAAAAGGAAACAUGCUAGAAAACGUGCCUAGAGAAGACACUUCAACCUUUGCCUUAUCCAACCCCUCUUCAGAGAAAGGUGUCCCAUGGCCCCAAAAAGAACUGCCAAGUUUUGGUGAGGAGUAACACCCUGGCAUGACAUUCCUUCUCUUUCCUGGCCCUCAACCACUUCCUUCCUUUGGCUCUUAAGACCUAGCAGGUUCUGUGAACUCUCAGGCCUUGGCCAGCACUAGUUAGGGGAGGUCAGGUGGUCAAUGUCCUGGUGAUUUUAUGAGACUGCCCCACUGAGAAAACUUACUUACUUCAGGCAUCCAGUGCCCCCACCCAGGGUUCAGGCCCUGUCUAAGGUGUUGCUUAAAGACAAAAAGGCAACAUGUGCCUCACUGGUGGUGUGCCACUGUUCUCAUGCUGCCUCCUAAGUGACUCCGAUUUUCAGCCCUGGUAGAAUAAGGAAGACAGCUGAUGCCUCCUUAGCCCCUUAGCACAUGUUCCUAAGGUGUGUUGUCAAGCCAACCUGAAUUCUGCCUCCCUGUUAUAGUCCCUGUCUCCCCCACAGAGACCUGUGGGUGCUCCCAGCAGAGUUGAGACUGGCUCCGUUGAGUUAAUGACUAGAAUAUAGUGCUUUCACUACUUGAUUGUUAACCUGUUUUCUUCUGAUGCCAUCAGUACCAGCAGUCAGACUAUUCCACUGGUUAAGUGUUUACUACCAUUAAAGCGAGGCAUGAAGCAAAGAGCUGAGUGAGUCCUCUGCUCUCCAGAGGACCAAGAAAUACCUGUGUGACACAGACCCACUUCAGUGUGUACAGCAAAUUCUAUAGUGCUUCUGAGCCCAGCAGGGCUUUACCUGCCCCUGGAGAGUUUUAGCCGUCUUGUGUUUCUUGUUUACUUCACAACCAAAUUUGUCCCCUCUUCUCUCUGUUAAGGGAGAGAAGUCACUUUAGCUGGAUAAUACCUAUGUAACAAACUGAGCAGCUGUUAUUUGGGCAAAAUCAAAGGAAGAAAGAGACUAUGGUCUUCUAUUUAUUGUGGGAAGGAAAACAGGGUGGGGCGGGUGAGUGAAAAGGUGGAAAUCCCUGGUACCUUGCCUGGUGGUUACACAGUUUAACCAUAGGCCAAUUUUAGGGGCCUCUGAAGUAUCUUUCUACAAACGCAGACAAGCUCCACUACCCCUAACCUGCCAGGAUGCUCAAGUCCACUGUCACAAUCCCUUUCAGAAAACAUUAGUGGCCGCUGCCCCAGCUACAGAGACGGCCGAAAUGCUUUCACUCCUUAGCUUUGCCAACUCCAUCCUCCAAAACUUCCCAGAAUACCUCCCUUUCCAGUUCUACCAAAUCUGUACUUGGGAGCAGCCUGCUGGAUCCAGAACAUGACAACAGAGAGCUGCGUCCACAGGGAACAAAGCCCUGACCUCUCUCUCCACAUUACCCUUACAAAAACAGGCCCUCCCCAUGAGAGAGCUACACGGCAGGGGCAGACACUGUGAGUAUAAGCUACUUUCCUCCCUGGAGUGCUCUAUGUGGGCAGAACAUGCUCUCCUUGCCUCUCCUGGAAGGUGUCUUCUCUAUGGCCUGGCUAGAGCUGCAAAAAAGGGACACACCCCACUUCGGUAAAAGAAAAUAGGGAAAGGCCAUAAACAAAGACAGACUUGUAGUUUAUUUUGUAUUUUUUUUAAAUAAAUACACUUUACAUUAAAGAAAAA